GCAGUUGCGCCCGGCAGCGACGGGAAACGUCUCUGAAUUAGGUGUUCCGCUCGCCUCUUGUGCGGUGUGGAGCUGCGCGCCCCCCGCCGAGGCGGGCCCAGGUACAGGCUGCCGGUGAGGGCGGGCCCGGGGCGUGCGGCUGCCGCGGCGGGACCAGGACGAGGGCUGGCCUCUGCGCGUGUCUGCCGAGUCCCCGGCUCCGGGCGUCCGAGCCGGGGCGGCCUCGGCAGGUGAACCCGGCCCCGGAGGGGGCGUGGCCUGGGAAGGGCCUGGCGGAGGCCGGGAGGGCGCUUCGACGCCGCUGGACUCCUGGGCCGCAGCCUGGGCCGGACUCCGGGGGAAACGGCUCCAGAACAGAAACUGCAAAAUGCCGCCUCGGUUCAGGGUCCGGAGCCCUCCGGGCGGUUUUUCGCUCUUAGUGUUUGUGGGUUUAAGCCUCCCCCUACUCCGUUUCCCGGAGUUUAAACUUUAGAUUUACUCGUUUUUGGCAGUCUUGCACGUUUGGCAGUGUUUUCCUACAGCCAGUCCUAGAGUGAUUUAACUAUUUCUUUUUUUAUUUACCGUAACCAUGUCCACUUGCUACGUUUCUUCCCAUUUCUCUAAAUUUUAAAUCAAUUUCUAGCUAGUGAUGCUGUUUUCUUGCGCCCUUGUUUUUUUGGGGCCAGGGAGAAUGGGUAACGCUACCUUUAAGCAGCUUUGAUAACUGUUUUUGAUAAAGGAAGUAAAUCUUACAAGAGGAAGAAAAGAGGACUAAUUUUUGGUUGGCUGUUCCUAAAAAAGAGCAUCAGUUCUUCAACUGCUGUUUUUCGUAUUGAACAACAUCCAAGUGCAGAUGUGUGGAAUAUUGUGUCAUUUCCUAUUACUUUAUCUGAAUGAGCCUUGCCUGAUUCUGCCCUUGACCCUGUUAAGGCACGGCAGAUGGUCUUCAUCCCUUCGCUCCUUUCGUCUUUAUCGUAAAGCACUGGCAGAAAGGUAGCAGGCCCGGUGACUCUGAACCUGCUUCCCACACUGGUUUAAGUGGCCGGACUUAGGGCCCCUCUGGCCUGGGCAGUUCCAGGCUCCUUCUCUGCAGGUGCUCAGCUUAUGGCUUCUAACCUGGUCUGGCCUAAUGAGGGUGGGCAUGCAGGCUGGAUGAAAAGACCUCACAGCUUUUUUCUCCAUUCCAGGUGCCUUCUCCAAGAGAGGCAGCAGGGAGGGAGAAAUGGCAAGGAGGUUGCUGCCAGCCCAUGUACAGGAGUCCGUGACGUUCAGGGAUGUGGCCGUGUUCUUCAGCCAGGACGAGUGGUUGCACCUGGACUCUGCCCAGAGAGCCUUGUACCGGGAGGUGAUGCUGGAGAACUACAGCAUCCUGGUCUCACUGGGGAUUCUCUUUUCCAAGCCAAAGGUCAUCUCCCAGUUAGAGCAAGGAGAAGACCCCUGGAUGGUGGAGAGUGGAGUUCCCCAAGGCGCACAUCUCGGAUGGGAAAGCUUGUUUGGAACCAUAGUUUCUAAAGAAGAAAAUCAGGAAGUCAUGAAAAAACUCAUAAUUGAUGGCACAUUUGACUUCAAGUUGGAGAAGACCUACAUAAAUGAAGAUAAGUUAGAGAAGCAACAAGGCAAAAAGAACAGACUUUUCAGUAAAGUGUUAGUUACCAUCAAAAAAGUCUACAUGAAGGAGAGGAGCUUUAAAGGUGUUGAAUUUGGGAAAAAUCUUGGUCUAAAAUCAUCGCUUAUUAGAAAACCGAGAAUAGUUUCCAGAGGAAGGAGACCCCGUUCACAGCAGUAUUCAGUUCUCUUUAAACAACUGGGGGUCAACACAGUGCGUAAAUGUUAUAAAUGUAAUAUCUGUGGGAAAAUCUUCCUCCACAGUUCCUCCCUGAGUAAACACCAGAGAAUCCACACUGGAGAGAAGCUCUAUAAAUGUAAGGAAUGUAGGAAAGCCUUCAGCCAAAGCUCAUCCCUAACUCAGCACUUGAGGGUUCAUACAGGAGAGAAACCUUAUAUAUGUAGUGAAUGUGGAAAAGCCUUCAGUUUCACCACAUCUCUUAUUGGACACCAGAGAAUGCAUACUGGAGAGAGACCUUAUAAAUGCAAGGAAUGUGGAAAAACAUUUAAAGGUAGUUCAUCUCUUAAUAAUCACCAGCGAAUUCACACAGGAGAGAAGCCCUAUAAGUGUAAUGAAUGUGGGAGGGCCUUCAGUCAGUGCUCAUCUCUCAUUCAGCACCACAGAAUUCAUACUGGGGAGAAACCGUAUGAAUGUACUCAGUGUGGGAAAGCCUUCACUUCAAUAUCGCGGCUAAGUAGGCACCAUCGAAUUCAUACUGGAGAGAAACCCUUUCAUUGUAACGAGUGUGGAAAAGUAUUCAGCUAUCACUCAGCCCUUAUCAUACAUCAGAGAAUUCACACUGGUGAGAAACCAUAUGCAUGCAAAGAAUGUGGGAAAGCCUUCAGCCAAAGCUCAGCUCUCAUACAACAUCAAAGAAUUCACACUGGAGAAAAACCCUACAAAUGUAAUGAAUGUGGGAAAGCCUUCUCUUGGAUUUCACGGCUUAAUAUACAUCACAGAAUUCACACUGGAGAGAAACCAUAUAAUUGUAAGGAAUGUGGAAAAGCCUUCAGUUCCCACUCAGGCGUUAAUACUCAUCGAAAAAUUCAUACUGGAGAAAAACCUUAUAAAUGUAAUGACUGUGAGAAAGCCUUCAACCAAAGCUCAGCUCUAAUUCAGCACCAGAGAAUUCAUACUGGAGAGAAACCAUAUAAUUGUAAAGUGUGUGGGAAAGCCUUCAGACAGAGUUCAUCCCUUAUGACACACAUGAGAAUUCAUACAGGGGAAAAACCUUAUAAAUGUAAAGAAUGUGGGAAGGCUUUUAGUCAGAGCUCAUCUCUUACUAAUCAUCAAAGGACUCAUAAUUGAGAAAAACUGUAUAAAUGCAUGUAGGAACUGAAGUUAUAUUCCAUACUGAGUAUCAAAAAAUUCAUUGUGGGGAGAAAGUGAUGAAGAGUAGUUAAUCAUAGGUAAAACUUCAGCAUUAGACCUCAUCACACAUCAGAGACUUCAUGAUGCAGGGUAACCUUGGGAAUGCUAGAAAAGCUUCUAUAAAAUGUUUAUUCAUAUGUUCUUAAGUUAUUACCAUGAAAUGGAGAAUUUUUAAGAUUGCAGGGUUAGUAUUUGAUUGUCUAGUGAUGUACGAUAACAGCCACCAGCUUUCCUGAGCAUCACUGGGAAGCCUGCUGUUUAUGUACAAGUACAGCCAUAAAAUCCAGACACAGAUAAAUCUAGGAAUCUAUUUUUUGAAACUAUUAUGCAAGCCAGUGGUACUAGAAAGAAUGUUUUAGAAAAGAAAUAUGUACAGGUGACCCAUAGCUACCUCACUGUCACUAAAAUGUUUUUUAAUAAUCUUAAAGCAGAUUCUGCACUUCAUGGUAAAGACUUUGAAUUGUUUCUCUGCUUUCUAAGCCAUUCACCUGAGAAGAAAAUCACUCCAUAAACUAUGCAGACGUACUGUCUUUGCGUUUUCUUCCUGACUACUUGUUCCAAACUCUGAGUCAGAUCUAAAGUCACUUUAAGUCACAGAACGCAUGGUAUUUCACUUGUUUUUCUCAUUAAAAGUGAUUACCUUUGCUGUAUUAAAUUGAUAAGUAAAGGUCAUUCAGACAACCACUGCUUUUGCAAUUUACUGAAAAAUGUUAUAAAUUAUCUCAGAAUGUAGCCAAUAGCAAGCACAGCUCAGCUCCCAGGGUCUGCCUGCUUCUGUGAGCUUUCUGGUUACCAGCCACCAGAAGGCCCAGGAACAAUGUAGAACUCAGGUCAUCAUCCUUGGAGGUAAAAUGAACCAGAUGAUUUUCACCCUUACUUCCACUUUUUCGCCUUCAUCAGACAAGGUUCACUUUCUCCCCACACUCUAAAGGUCACUGGGCAAAUAUUUAGGCUCUGAGUUCAGAUACUCUUUCUUCCAGCAAAUGGACUUACACUCUUCAACAAGUGAUUUAGCUCAUUUCAGCAUUUCUAAAAUGUGAAUCAUAAGAUUAGCAAGCUAAAAACAGUUAUCUCACAAGUCAAAAUUGUUGGGCUUUACAGAGGCUAACAUCUAGUUUAGCCAAGUUUAUCAGGAGGGGGCAAGCACUUAAGGGCUGAAACGACCCAUUUCAUAAAGUGCUAAGUUUUUCUGCCAAGGAACUUUAAAAAAUAGAAAACUGGCUGGGUGCAGUGGCUCACGCCUGUAAUCCCGGCACUUUGGGAGGCCAAGACGGGCAGAUCAUGAGGUCAGGAGAUCGAGACCAUCCUGGCUAACAUGGUGAAACCACGUCUCCACUAAAAAUACAAAAAAAAAAAAAAAA